GCACACGCUGGUCACGCGGUCAGCUAUUGACACUUCCUGGUGGGAUCCGAGUGAGGCGACGGGGUAGGGGUUGGCGCUCAGGCGGCGACCAUGGCGUAUCACGGCCUCACUGUGCCUCUCAUUGUGAUGAGCGUGUUCUGGGGCUUCGUCGGCUUCUUGGUGCCUUGGUUCAUCCCUAAGGGUCCUAACCGGGGAGUUAUCAUUACCAUGUUGGUGACCUGUUCAGUUUGCUGCUAUCUCUUUUGGCUGAUUGCAAUUCUGGCCCAACUCAACCCUCUCUUUGGACCGCAAUUGAAAAAUGAAACCAUCUGGUAUCUGAAGUAUCAUUGGCCUUGAGGAAGAAGACAUGCUCUACAGUGCUCAGUCUUUGAGGUCACGAGAAGAGAAUGCCUUCUAGAUGCAAAAUCACCUCCAAACCAGACCACUUUUCUUGACUUGCCUGUUUUGGCCAUUAGCUGCCUUAAACGUUAACAGCACAUUUGAAUGCCUUAUUCUACAAUGCAGCGUGUUUUCCUUUGCCUUUUUUGCACUUUGGUGAAUUACGUGCCUCCAUAACCUGAACUGUGCCGACUCCACAAAACGAUUAUGUACUCUUCUGAGAUAGAAGAUGCUGUUCUUCUGAGAGAUACGUUACUCUCUCCUUGGAAUCUGUGGAUUUGAAGAUGGCUCCUGCCUUCUCACGUGGGAAUCAGUGAAGUGUUUAGAAACUGCUGCAAGACAAACAAGACUCCAGUGGGGUGGUCAGUAGGAGAGCACGUUCAGAGGGAAGAGCCAUCUCAACAGAAUCGCACCAAACUAUACUUUCAGGAUGAAUUUCUUCUUUCUGCCAUCUUUUGGAAUAAAUAUUUUCCUCCUUUCUAUGGAAAUCUGGGCUCGGUGUUUGUAAAGUUCAUUUUUAUAAGCUUUUCUAUCGCUACAUAAUGCCUUUUUAAAAAAUGAUUUUGUAGUCUAAACUUAGGUUGAGUAUAUAAACCCUGCCAUGUAGCUUGAGAUGCCUGAAAAGACUGGUAAGUGCGUUUCUUAAUCGUUCAGUAACUAUUUGAGUGCCUACUGCAGCCAAGGCACUGGAGGGAUCAAAGAUGUGUAAAUUUGGAGUCCCUGCAAGUUCACAAGCUAUUUGGAGAGAUAAGGUUAGUAUACAUAGAACUGUAAUAUAAGGUUGUGUUGGAGCAUUGUCCUUAAAGAUGGUACCAUGGUGAGCAGUUCAAGGUUACCUGCCAGCUGCAGAACAAGGCAGCAAAUGCUCCUGAGAUGGAACCAUCACAGCCUCAGACAUAGGACUAAAGAAGUCAAGAGUGAUUAAAAAGCCAGGGGCAGGAGACAGUAAUUUUGUAUUUCAGUAGCAGGCAUCUCGAUACACUAAUUUGAGAGCUUUAUUACUUUUAAGAAAUUAAAAAUUAAAAUGAACCUAAAUUUUCA